AGUCAGUCCGCGGCGCCACAAGCCUCAGUGUUUACUUCUGCCGCCUGCCAGCCGGGCGGGGAAGGGGAGUACCCGGCCACCCCUCACUUUAGCUCCUGCAGCUUUCCAAACAAACCAGGGCGGGAUGGGAGUGUCUUCUUGGCUGUGGAAAUCGAUCCUCCUACCUUGUCCUGAAGCCACCCGCCGCCUUUCCUCGUCCCUCCCUUCGCGGUGAUUUUCCGGUCCCGGCGCCCGGCGAGGGCGCGCGGCUGGUGUCCGCCCCGCCCGAAAGCAUUUGCAAGUGAGGAAGCAGCACAACCCUGGGUUUUAGAUAAUUUCUAACAGAGAGGCCCCAGCAAUUCAGCAGGCAGCGUCCUGAGUCUUUGGCAGCCUGGUCCCUCUUUCGCAAAUUCUCCACCUUUGCGAACAGAGGGUCUUUAGGACACAGAUUCUUAAAAGUGCAGGUGAGCCAGCCAUGAGAGGGUAUCUUGUGGCCAUAUUCCUGAGUGCUGUCUUCCUCUAUUAUGUACUGCAUUGCAUAUUAUGGGGAACGAAUGUCUAUUGGGUGGCACCUGUGGAAAUGAAACGGAGAAAUAAGAUCCAGCCUUGUUUAUCAAAGCCAGCUUUUGCCUCUCUGCUGAGUCAGAGCUCUGCAUAUAUUUUAAGAAAAGGCAUUGAGGAACUCAAUCAAACCAGUAUUCUUUUCACACAGGUUUCAUCAGUUUCACCCUUUUCUGUGUGCGGCUGAUUUUAGAAAGAUUGCUUCCUUGUAUGGUAGCGAUAAGUUUGAUUUGCCCUAUGGGAUGAGAACAUCAGCGGAAUAUUUUCGACUUGCUCUUUCAAAACUGCAGAGUUGUGAUCUCUUUGAUGAGUUUGACAACAUACCCUGUAAAAAGUGUGUGGUGGUUGGUAAUGGAGGAGUUUUGAAGAAUAAGACAUUAGGAGAAAAAAUCGACUCCUAUGAUGUAAUAAUAAGAAUGAAUAAUGGUCCUGUUUUAGGACAUGAAGAAGAAGUUGGGAGAAGGACAACCUUCCGACUUUUUUAUCCAGAAUCUGUUUUUUCAGAUCCUAUUCACAAUGACCCUAAUACGACAGUGAUUCUCACUGCUUUUAAGCCACAUGAUUUAAGGUGGCUGUUGGAAUUGUUGAUGGGUGACAAAAUAAACACUAAUGGUUUUUGGAAGAAACCAGCCUUAAACCUGAUUUAUAAACCUUAUCAAAUCCGAAUAUUAGAUCCUUUCAUUAUCAGAACAGCAGCUUAUGAACUGCUUCAUUUUCCAAAAGUGUUUCCCAAAAAUCAGAAACCUAAACACCCAACAACAGGAAUUAUUGCCAUCACAUUGGCGUUUUACAUAUGUCACGAAGUUCACCUAGCUGGUUUUAAAUACAACUUUUCUGACCUCAAGAGUCCUUUGCACUACUAUGGGAAUGCCACCAUGUCUUUGAUGAAUAAGAACGCGUAUCACAAUGUGACUGCAGAGCAGCUCUUUUUGAAGGACAUUAUAGAAAAAAACCUCGUAAUCAACUUGACUCAAGAUUGACUCUACAGACUCAGAAGAUGAUGCUAACAGUGUUAGUUUUAUUUUUGUACUGCAAUUUUUAGUUUAAAAUAUGUUGGAUGCACUCGUCAAAUAAUUAUGUAUACUGUCUGUUGCUGCCUGGUGAUUCAUAACCACCAGCUUAAUUUCUGUGAAUACUGUAUAUUUAACUUAUGAAAACCAAGAAAUGUAAAGAUAACAGGAAAAUAAGUUUUGAUUGCAUUGUUUUUAAAAUAAGCUAGUUUUCUGAGGUGUUUUCACACGUCUUUUUAUAGUUACUUCAUCUUAGAUUUUUGAAGGGAUAUGACUUCCUACUAAGGAUUUAGUUUACCACAACAAUUCUGACUACAAUAAGACAUUUUGAGGAGGAUAUUUGGCUACUGUAAACAUGGCUGGUGGAAAAUCACGAUUGUGGCUUGAUGUGGCAAGCCGAAACCACUUGGCUCUGGAAAUCUAAGUUCAUACUGGUUUAAUUAAGCUCUCUCCUGACAACCCCCAGAAUUAAAUGAACCAUGAUUGUGAAGAGUAAUUUGGUACAAUGAAGGCAGUGUUUGUUUUUAAGUUAAAGGAAAUGGGCUAAACAUAAAGUUCUUAUUAGAUAAGUAAAUAACUAAAGAAAGAAUACAAUUACUAAACUCUGAUGGCUUUGUAUUAUUUUAAAGAAAUGAAGUUUAACUUUAUACAGUGAAGCUAAGCUAGGCAAGCUCAAGAAGGAAAAAAAAAUCUUGAACAUUAUUUUUUUUUGCCUGACUUACUUAUUCAUUAAAUUUUGAAGGUUUUCCACUUGAAGUAAAUUAGGAAAGGUAAAGAAGAUAACAGAACAAGUAAACACUUAAGAAAAGUCAAGCUGAGGCCGGGCAGGGUGGCUCACACCUGUAAUCCUAACAAACACUUUGGGAGGCCGAGGGAGGCAGCUGGAUUGCCUGAACUCAGGAGUUCAAGACCAGCCUGGCCAACAUGGUGAAACCUCAUCUCUACUAAAAUACAAAAUAAUUAGCUGGGCGUGGUGGUAUGCGCUGUAGUCCCAGGUACUCGGGAGGCUGAGGCACGAGAAUUGCUUGAGCCCGGGAGGCAGAGGUUGCAGUGAGCCAAGAUCGCGCCACUGCACUUCAGCCUGGGUGACAGAGUGAGGCUGUCUUCUAAAAAAUAUAAAAAGUGAAGUUGGGAUUUUUGGAUUUAAAUGGUACAAAAAGAAUAUCUCAUUUUCCCAUGAUUAAAGCUAAUCUUCAGAUGGAAAGCUUGCCUGGCUACCUAGGGUGCACCAGAGAAUCUGAUCCAAUGCAAGCCAGUCAAUCCUACAAAUGUGGUGAGCUAGUCUUCCUUCCUAUAUUUUAAUAAAUGUAACCAAAGGCCAUCUGGAGGUAGGGGAAUGAGAGGUGAAGAAACAGAAAAAUAGAGGUUAUAAGGAUGGAACUAAAAGUUGUCAGAAGAGGUAUGAGCUGAAGAAAGAAUUACUCUCUUUUGACCAAUAAAUACAAUUGGGAAACACUGGAAAACCAUGGCUUGAUUACUGACAACCAACCUGCCUCUCUAAAGAGGGUGUAUAAAGGGUGAAAUACAUUAGAUUUGGCUCAGAAACAGAAUGCGGUACUUAUAAAGCAGAAUAAAGGGGAGAACAGUAGUAGUUGAUCUAACCCAGAUUAGACAUGAAUACCAGCAUAUGUUUGCAGAGUCCCACAGUUUUGAUUCCUCUUAUAACUUUUUGAGGUGCAAAAGGAAGGUACCAGAACUGGAAUCACAUGUAAUCAAUCAGUGUGAUUUUCCCCUCAUACCACACAGCCAUAGGCUGCAGUGUGGCUGCUGAAGUUCAAUUGAUAUAAAGUAAAUCAGGCUUCAAAAAGAAUGGUGCUGUGGGUACACAAGGACAUAAAGAUGGGAACGAUAGACACUGAGGACUGCGGCGGGGGGAGCGAGGGGAGCGGGGAGGGCAAGGGCUGAAAGACUAUGUAUUGGGUACUAUGCUCACAACCUGGAUGAUGGGAUCAUUCAUACCACAAACCUCAGUAUCACACAAUAUACCCAUGUAACAACCUGCACUCUGCACAUGUACCCUUAGAAUCUAAAAUAAAAGUUGAAAUUAUUUUUUUAAAAAAA